AGAGACAAAGACCCCGAACACCUCCAACAUGAAGCUUCUUCAUGUUUUCCUGUUAUUUCUGUGCUUCCACUUAAGGUUUUGCAAGGUCACUUAUACAUCUCAAGAGGAUCUGGUGGAGAAAAAGUGCUUAGCAAAAAAAUAUACUCACCUCUCCUGCGAUAAAGUCUUCUGCCAGCCAUGGCAGAGAUGCAUUGAGGGCACCUGUGUUUGUAAACUACCGUAUCAGUGCCCAAAGAAUGGCACUGCAGUGUGUGCAACUAACAGGAGAAGCUUCCCAACAUACUGUCAACAAAAGAGUUUGGAAUGUCUUCAUCCAGGGACAAAGUUUUUAAAUAACGGAACAUGCACAGCCGAAGGAAAGUUUAGUGUUUCCUUGAAGCAUGGAAAUACAGAUUCAGAGGGAAUAGUUGAAGUAAAACUUGUGGACCAAGAUAAGACAAUGUUCAUAUGCAAAAGCAGCUGGAGCAUGAGGGAAGCCAACGUGGCCUGCCUUGACCUUGGGUUUCAACAAGGUGCUGAUACUCAAAGAAGGUUUAAGUUGUCUGAUCUCUCUAUAAAUUCCACUGAAUGUCUACAUGUGCAUUGCCGAGGAUUAGAGACCAGUUUGGCUGAAUGUACUUUUACUAAGAGAAGAACUAUGGGUUACCAGGAUUUCGCUGAUGUGGUUUGUUAUACACAGAAAGCAGAUUCUCCAAUGGAUGACUUCUUUCAGUGUGUGAAUGGGAAAUACAUUUCUCAGAUGAAAGCCUGUGAUGGUAUCAAUGAUUGUGGAGACCAAAGUGAUGAACUGUGUUGUAAAGCAUGCCAAGGCAAAGGCUUCCAUUGCAAAUCGGGUGUUUGCAUUCCAAGCCAGUAUCAAUGCAAUGGUGAGGUGGACUGCAUUACAGGGGAAGAUGAAGUUGGCUGUGCAGCAGCUAGACAUCCUACAAUUCAAGGCUUUGCAUCUGUGACUCAAGAAGAAACAGAAAUUUUGACUGCUGACAUGGAUGCAGAAAGAAGACGGAUAAAAUCAUUAUUACCUAAACUAUCUUGUGGAGUUAAAAACAGAAUGCACAUUCGAAGGAAACGAAUUGUGGGAGGAAAGCGAGCACAACUGGGAGACCUCCCAUGGCAGGUGGCAAUUAAGGAUGCCAGUGGAAUCACCUGUGGGGGAAUUUAUAUUGGUGGCUGUUGGAUUCUGACUGCUGCACAUUGUCUCAGAGCCAGUAAAACUCAUCGUUACCAAAUAUGGACAACAGUAGUAGACUGGAUACACCCCGACCUUAAACGUAUAGUAAUUGAAUACGUGGAUAGAAUUAUUUUCCAUGAAAACUACAAUGCAGGCACUUACCAAAAUGACAUCGCUUUGAUUGAAAUGAAAAAAGACGGAAACAAAAAAGAUUGUGAGCUGCCUCGUUCCAUCCCUGCCUGUGUCCCCUGGUCUCCUUACCUAUUCCAACCUAAUGAUACAUGCAUCGUUUCUGGCUGGGGACGAGAAAAAGAUAACGAAAGAGUCUUUUCACUUCAGUGGGGUGAAGUUAAACUAAUAAGCAACUGCUCUAAGUUUUACGGAAAUCGUUUCUAUGAAAAAGAAAUGGAAUGUGCAGGUUGCAAUCUCAUCUCAGUACUCAGUCGUAUAAAGUAGAGAACACAGGAAGAACAUGCUGAAUUGGGGGAAUAAAUAGAAGACUCGUAAAGAAUUUUCCAAGCUGCAUCUCUGCAACUCUGCAAGCCCAGCCAGGGACUCUAAGGAGAGCCCAUGCUAUUGCUGUCAGGAAACUGUAAAAAAGCCAAAGUUGUUAAAUGCCAUGGAGGAGGCAUGGCAGCCUUGAAAAAUGGAAGGAAAUGUGUGAUUUUCUCUUUCACAUUUCUUUCUUAGGUACAUAUGAUGGUUCCAUCGAUGCCUGUAAAGGGGACUCUGGAGGCCCCUUAGUCUGUAUGGAUGCCAACAAUGUGACUUAUGUCUGGGGUGUUGUGAGUUGGGGGGAAAACUGUGGAAAACCAGAGUUCCCAGGUGUUUACACCAAAGUGGCCAAUUAUUUUGACUGGAUUAGCUACCAUGUAGGAAGGCCUUUUAUUUCUCAGUACAAUGUAUAAAAUUGUGAUCUCUCUCUUCAUUCUAUUCUUUUUCUCUCAAGAGUUCCAUUUAAUGGAAAUAAAACGGUAUAAUUAAUAAUUCUCUAGGGGGGAAAAAUGAAGCAAAUCUCACUGGAUAUUUUUAAAGGUCUCCACAGAGUUUAUGCCAUAUUGGAAUUUUGUUGUAUAAUUCUCAAAUAAAUAUUUUGGUGAAGCAUA